CUGCAGGCCUCCGUGUCCCCUGGCUGCCGGCUAGGCAGUCCUGCUCUCUCGGGUCUGUGUUCUCAGCUUCGAGGUCCAGGCUGAGUGAGAGGAGCUCGGGCGGCUCCAGGCACUUCUUCCCUUGAGUGGGUGGACUACUGAGGUCCCCUGGGCACGGCGUCAUGGUGCGGAACGUGGAUGACCUGGAUUUCCACCUGCCCUCGCAUGCCCAGGACAUGCUGGAUGGCCUGCAGCGCCUGCGCUCUCAGCCCAAGCUGGCCGACGUCACACUGCUGGUGGGCGGCCGGGAGCUGCCAUGCCACCGCGGCCUCCUGGCGCUCAGCAGCCCCUACUUCCAUGCCAUGUUUGCGGGUGACUUCGCCGAGAGCUUCUCUGCGCGCGUGGAGCUGCGGGACGUGGAGCCCGCCGUGGUGGGACAACUGGUGGACUUCGUGUACACAGGCCGGCUGACCAUCACGCAGGGCAACGUGGAGGCGCUGACACGCACGGCUGCGCGCCUGCACUUCCCCUCGGUGCAGAAGGUCUGCGGCCGCUACCUGCAGCAGCAACUGGAUGCCGCCAACUGCCUGGGCAUCUGUGAGUUCGGGGAGCAGCAAGGGCUGCUGGGCGUGGCUGCCAAGGCCUGGGCCUUCCUGCGAGAGAACUUUGAGGCUGUGGCACGUGAGGACGAGUUCCUGCAGCUUCCCCGAGAGCGGCUGGUCACUUGUCUGGCCGGCGACCUGCUGCAGGUACAGCCGGAGCAAAGCCGACUCGAGGCCCUGAUGCGCUGGGUGCGCCAUGACCCGCAGGCCCGGGCCGCCCACCUGCCCGAGCUGCUCAGCCUAGUGCACCUGGACGCCGUGCCCAGGCCCUGCGUGCAGCAACUGCUGGCCUCAGAGCCCCUGAUCCAGGAGUCAGAGGCAUGCCGGGCAGCCCUGUCCCAGGGCCAUGAUGGGGCACCACUCGCCCUCCAGCAGAAGCUGGAGGAGGUCCUGGUGGUGGUGGGCGGGCAGGCGCUGGAGGAGGAGGAGGCAGGUGAGGAGCCCACCCCCGGCCUUGGGAACUUUGCCUUCUACAACAGCAAGGCCAAGAGGUGGAUGGCACUUCCAGACUUCCCCGACUAUCACAAGUGGGGUUUCUCCCUGGCGGCCCUGAACAACAACAUCUAUGUCACAGGUGGCUCUCGGGGCACAAAGACAGACACCUGGUCAACCACCCAGGCCUGGUGCUUCCCCCUGAAGGAGGCCUCCUGGAAGCCCGUGGCGCCCAUGCUGAAGCCCCGCACCAACCACGCCAGCGCGGCCCUCAAUGGGGAGAUCUACGUUAUCGGCGGCACCACCCUGGACGUGGUGGAGGUGGAGAGCUAUGACCCCUACACGGACAGCUGGACGCCCGUCAGCCCGGCCCUCAAAUACGUCAGCAACUUCUCGGCUGCCGGCUGCCGGGGCCGGCUCUACCUGGUGGGCUCCAGCGCCUGCAAGUACAACGCCCUGGCCCUGCAGUGCUACAACCCUGUCACAGAUGCGUGGAGUGUGAUCGCCUCGCCCUUCCUGCCCAAGUACCUGUCCUCGCCUCGCUGUGCUGCACUGCACGGGGAGCUCUACCUCAUUGGGGACAACACCAAGAAGGUCUACGUGUACGACCCCGGGGCCAACCUGUGGCAGAAGGUGCAGUCACAGCACAGCCUGCAUGAGAAUGGCGCGCUGGUGCCACUGGGUGAUGCGCUGUACGUGACGGGCGGCCGCUGGCAGGGCAUGGAAGGUGACUACCACGUGGAGAUGGAGGCCUACGACACGGUUCGGGACACCUGGACCCGCCACGGCGCCCUGCCCCGGCUCUGGCUCUACCACGGGGCCUCCACCGUCUUCCUGGAUGUCUCCAAGUGGACCCAGCCCUCCGGCCCCACCCAGGAGCACUAAACCAGGGCCAGGGUCCCCGGGGAGGAGUCCCCACAGCGGCCCCUCAUCAGCCUGUGGAACGGCCCCUUUCAUUUUCGCUUAUUUGUUCACUCGGAGCUACCAUUCCUUCCAAGCUGCGCUCAGGCCACCAGGGGUGAUCAGACGGCAUGGCUUGGAGGACACAGCCUUGGUCUCUGUGGCCACCACACUAAACUCUGAGCUGAGCAGUGACAAGGGCCUGAGUGCCAGACGCUGGCAUAACAGGGACAGGAAGCUCUGCUGCCCCUGGGGUUCCCGAGACCUCAGAGAGGGGAGCCGGGGGCCGGGCCAGCAUUCCCAGAGCUUGCGAGCCCCACUCCUGCCCCUGGACCCCAGCAGGGGCUUUUGGAGCAGUUGCAUGAAUGUGGGGUGAACACGGAGCGUCCCAGAAAGCUGAGGCUGCUGGGGAAGGCAGGCCCCGGAGAUGGGAUCAGCACCAGGUCCUCGUGGGCCUGCUUCUGCCCAGCUCACGGCAGCGUAACUGUGGCCAGCCACCUCCCCUCUCUGGGCUUCAAGCUCCGCGUCCACCACACACGGGGCUGGCUGUGUGGGCUUUGGGUCCCCACUCAGGCUUUGCAUGUUGGUGCUGUGUUUCUGCUUCUGUGGACAAAGGAGGCCCCCACCCAUCUCUUGCACCCAGAGGGCGGUGCCCACAGAGGCACCAGGAAGGAGGGAGGCAGGGCGUGGGGCGGGGCUGGAGGGUCCCAGGGAGGUGAGCAGUUUUGCUCUCAGAAGGGAUUGCCUCCGUCUCUGUGUGUCAGAACAAAGGCUCUUCAUUAGAAUGGAAUUUCCCACCAGGGGACGACUCUUGGGUGCAUUGGUGGCAGCCUCCUGAGGGUGAGGGGUAGCAUCCGAUGGGCCCCUGCCAGCAUGCAGCCCGACUCCGGCUGGCUCAGGCUCCGAGUGGCUUCUCCCUCAUCCUGAAUGAGGCACCCACCUUUGCAGCUAAGGAGACAAUGAAGGACUCUCCCUGGGUGCCCAAUGGCGUGUCCCUCCUGUCACAGGCUCCGCCCUGGGACAUGGGGCUAGAAGUCAGGAGUCGGGCCCGGCCAGGCACAGGCCCUGGUGUUGCCCCAGAGGCCCUGGGCAGCUCCGGUCUCCCGCCGGAUCCAGGCUUCCUCUCCAGGACCAGCCCCUGGGUUCCUCCUUAACACCCCCCGCCCCUGGGGACCAGAGGGGCCUCUGACAUCCUUGGGUUCUGAGGACGGAAACCCCUGAGCCUCUUGAGCUUCUGUAGGUAGGGAUCUGCUUUGCUCCCAGACCUGCCUCUCAUAGCUUUUUUUUUUUUUUUUUUUUUUUUUUGAGACGGAGUCUCGCUCUUGUCGUCCAGGCUGGAGUGCAAUGCUGAGAUCUUGGCUCACUGCAACCUCCACCUCCCGGGUUCAAGAGAUUCUCCUGCCUUAGCCUCUCAAGUAGCUGGGAUUACAGGCACUCGCCACCACGCCUGACUAAUUUUUGUAUUUUUAGUAGAAACAGGGUUUCACCAUGUUGACCAGGCUGGUCUUGAACUCCUGACCUCAGGUGAUCCGCCCGCCUCAGCCUCCCAAAGUGCUGGGAUUACAAGGUGUGGGAGAAGUGAGUUGACCCUGGAGGGCCAGACAGAGUGGGGCCUCUGGGUGCUACCAAAGGAACAAGAGCCCAGAGCUGAGGAGACCUUCGGUGGCAGAUGGAUUGGAUGAAGCAAGGGUGAGGGUUUCUGGGGCCCUGGGCUCUGUUUCCAUGUGGAAAUCUGAAAUGUUUUCUAGACAGUGAUGGAAGGAGGUCAGCCAAAGGGCUGUUUAAAAACAAAGCCUCCAUGUAAACCAUUUCUGCAAGAAUAUUUUAAAAUAAAUAAAAAUAAAACUGAAGACAUGAAAUGUCAAAA